CAGAAACAGUGAACUUGAGUUUUUCGUUUUACCUUGAUCUCUCUCUGACAAAGAAAUCCAGAUGAUGCGAGACCUGAUGAAGACAAUACAUGGAAAAUGACAGUCUUGGAAAUAACUUUGGCUGUCAUCCUGACUCUACUGGGACUUGCCAUCCUGGCUAUUUUGUUAACAAGAUGGGCACGACGUAAGCAAAGUGAAAUGUAUAUCUCCAGAUACAGUUCAGAACAAAGUGCUAGACUUCUGGACUAUGAGGAUGGUAGAGAUUUUUCUUCUCAGAGAUCUAAAAGAGGAAGAGGAUCCCGACAUGCAUAUUCAACACAAAGUGACACUUCAUAUGAUAACCGAGAGAGAUCCAAAAGAGAUUACACACCAUCAACCAACUCUCUAGUGUCUAUGGCAUCUAAGUUCUCCCUGGGACAAACAGAACUCAUUCUUCUUUUGAUGUGUUUUAUUUUAGCACUGUCUCGAUCAAGUAUUGGUAGUAUAAAAUGUUUACAAACAACUGAAGAACCUCCUUCCAGAACUGCAGGAGCCAUGAUGCAAUUCACAGCCCCUAUUCCCGGAGCUACAGGACCUAUCAAGCUCUCUCAAAAAACCAUUGUGCAAACUCUAGGACCUAUUGUACAAUAUCCUGGAUCCAAUGCUGGUCCACCUUCAGCACCCCGCGGUCCACCCAUGGCACCCAUAAUAAUUUCACAGAGAACCGCAAGUCAGCUGGCAGCACCUAUAAUAAUUUCGCAGAGAACUGCAAGACAAAGACAUUGGUAUUUGAGUGAAGAGAAAUGGAACUGUCAACAAAGAAUUAUAAGAAUACCUCAAGUUCACACUAUGGACAGUUCUGGAAAAAUCACACUGACUCCUGUGGUUAUAUUAACAGGUUACAUGGAUGAAGAACUUGCAAAAAAAUCUUGUUCCAAAAUCCAGAUUCUAAAAUGUGGAGGCACUGCAAGGUCUCAGAAUAGCCGAGAAGAAAACAAGGAAGCACUAAAGAAUGACAUCAUAUUUACGAAUUCUGUAGAAUCCUUGAAAUCAGCACACAUAAAGGAGCCAGAAAGAGAAGGAAAAGGCACUGAUUUAGAGAAAGACAAAAUAGGAAUGGAGGUCAAGGUAGACAGUGACGCUGGAAUACCAAAAAGACAGGAAACCCAACUAAAAAUCAGUGAGAUGAGUAUACCACAAGGACAGGGAGCCCAAAUAAAGAAAAGUGUGUCAGAUGUACCAAGAGGACAGGAGUCCCAAGUAAAGAAGAGUGAGUCAGGUGUCCCAAAAGGACAAGAAGCCCAAGUAACGAAGAGUGGGUUGGUUGUACUGAAAGGACAGGAAGCCCAGGUAGAGAAGAGUGAGAUGGGUGUGCCAAGAAGACAGGAAUCCCAAGUAAAGAAGAGUCAGUCUGGUGUCUCAAAGGGACAGGAAGCCCAGGUAAAGAAGAGGGAGUCAGUUGUACUGAAAGGACAGGAAGCCCAGGUAGAGAAGAGUGAGUUGAAGGUACCAAAAGGACAAGAAGGCCAAGUAGAGAAGACUGAGGCAGAUGUGCCAAAGGAACAAGAGGUCCAAGAAAAGAAGAGUGAGGCAGGUGUACUGAAAGGACCAGAAUCCCAAGUAAAGAACACUGAGGUGAGUGUACCAGAAACACUGGAAUCCCAAGUAAAGAAGAGUGAGUCAGGUGUACUAAAAGGACAGGAAGCCCAAGAAAAGAAGGAGAGUUUUGAGGAUAAAGGAAAUAAUGAUAAAGAAAAGGAGAGAGAUGCAGAGAAAGAUCCAAAUAAAAAAGAAAAAGGUGACAAAAACACAAAAGGUGACAAAGGAAAGGACAAAGUUAAAGGAAAGAGAGAAUCAGAAAUCAAUGGUGAAAAAUCAAAAGGCUCGAAAAGGGCGAAGGCAAAUACAGGAAGGAAGUACAACAAAAAAGUGGAAGAGUAAGGAUAAAUUUUUUAAAGGCCCAUAAGACAAGUGAUUAUUAUGAUUCCCAUACUCCAGAUACAAACCAUAUCCCAGCCAUUGCCUAAACAGAUUACAAUUAUAAAAUCCCUUUCAUCUUCAUAUCACAGUUUCUGCUCUUCAGAAGUUUCACCCUUUUUAAUCUCUCAGCCACAAACCUCAGUUUCCAAAUAUUUGUUUUAUAAGUUAAGACGUAUAUGAUUCCGUCAAGAAAGACUGGAUACUUUCUGAAGUAAAACAUUUUAAUUAAAGAAAUAUAUAGUAAU